CUCCAUUUCUCACCUUUUUCCCAAGAGGACACACAUACCCCGCUCAACUUGACGCCUAAAGCAGCCGCUUCCAGGCCUGGGGUUUCGGAUAGGCCAAGCCGGCUGCUGCCGACCCGCACGCCGCCCCGGGCCCCGGCUCCUCUCUAGGCGGUGGCCGCGCCGUCGCCUGCUCGGCUGCGGGAUGCUUGCUCCCAAGGUCCCAGGCGUCCAGGUUGAUCGCCAGCCCCUUACCCUGGUGAGGGAGGCCUUGCGCCCUGCAGAAGCCCCGGGCCCUGCGGCGGCGGCGGCGGCAUCCUCCUGGUCGCCUCCUCGCUUUCCUCCACCCGAGCUCCGCCGGCUGCUCCUUGGGAGGAAGGGGACUCGCUAGACCAGGCCGAGGCCCAGCCUCAGAAGUCAGCAUUUUCAAGACCUGGCAUCCGCAGCGUUUCUGACGCGGGGACUUCUCUCUUCGGCUCUGAGGUCUCCGCGCGCAGAACCCAUGGCAGCUUUUGGUCUUACGCGUGGCUGUGAGCUGGGCUCACGCUGCGUGGCGCAUCCACCCCUCGAUUGACGCGCGGAGAAGCAUUUUUCAUUUUUUCUUUCAGCUUGUAUCCUUAAAUCUUAAUCCCGGGCUUCUUAGCAAAAAUGCGUGUGCAUUCGUUUCUCCUUGUUUAUGGAGAGGUUUCCGGUGAAUGUUAGACAGCAACUAAAUAAUUAAAAGGUUUAGAGAGCGCUGUGAGCAGGAGAAGAUGCGGGCAGCCUGGCUGGCCCAGGAGAGACGAGUGGUCAGAGAAUGAAAGGAAAAUCGAUGCCUCUUAACUGGGCCGCCUAAUAACGGGAGACCAAGUGGGCUCAGGAGAAACGUGGCGGGGGGGGGGGGAGCUUUCUUUAAAAAAUUGGGGUUCUUUCUUUCUGUCCUAUAUAUGGAAAUUCAGCCCUGAUUUCAAACAAACAUCAGAUUUAAGAAGGUGAGGACUCCAAAGAAGAUCCAAACGCGAGACCAGGAAGAUUCACGUUUCCACUACUUCUUCCAAUACAUUUCACUAAUCUUUCUACAGGGAUAGUGUUUUAAAACACGACGACCCUCACACACCAAGGUGAAGUUGAAUAUUGUUGUUGUUCCUUCACCGCAUGAAAGGAAUCCUUCAGAACUUACUUUCAGGGACGGCUUCUUCUAUCUCGAAUUUUUGCAUUUGUAGGGAAUUUUAUGGGGUAGAGGAGCGAAGAGGGAACAAUGUCUCCAAUUCAAAUAAAACCCCAAAUUAAGCUCUCAGCCCCAUCGGUGGGAUAGCCUGCGGGGGAACCCACUCCCUCUCCUGGCAGCAUUGCCCUGGGGGCGAGCAGAGAGUGGAUUUGGAGUCUUCUUUUCCCGCCUGACCCCUGCUCGCCCGAGCAGCAUUUUCGGGCCAGCGGCUGCAGCCACCCGGGCGCCGCUAGGGGAUGCAGUGGCUCAAAGGACCGAGCGGGCGGUGCAGGUUGGAACCCGCGGGGCGGACCAAUCGCGGCUCGGCCACAGCCUCGCCCGCUGAUUGGUCCCUCCAGGCCCCGCCCCCGCUCGCCCCGCCCCUCUCGCUGGGGCGCCUCGGAGCCGCGUGCCCUCCGCCCCGGGGUGCCCAUUGCGCAGAGCGUGGCCUGGAGACCCGCGAGCCGGGGAAGGUCGCCGUGGAGUCCCGACCAGAGGCCGGGGUUGGGGUCGGUGCAGACCGAGGGCUGGUUUCCUUGACUGUGGGAGAAACGCCGGGAGCCGGAGUGACCCGAGGAGGGACUCCGCCUCCGAGCGGCUGAGGACCCCGGUGCAGAGGAGCCUGGCUCGCAGAAUUGCAGAGUCGUCGCCCCUUUUUACAACCUGGUCCCGUUUUAUUCUGCCGUACCCAGUUUUUGGAUUUUUGUCUUCCCCUUCUUCUCUUUGCUAAACGACCCCUCCAAGAUAAUUUUUAAAAAACCUUCUCCUUUGCUCACCUUUGCUUCCCAGCCUUCCCAUCCCCCCACCGAAAGCAAAUCAUUCAACGACCCCCGACCCUCCGACGGCAGGAGCCCCCCGACCUCCCAGGCGGACCGCCCUCCCUCCCCGCGCGCGGGUUCCGGGCCCGGCGAGAGGGCGCGAGCACAGCCGAGGCCAUGGAGGUGACGGCGGACCAGCCGCGCUGGGUGAGCCACCACCACCCCGCCGUGCUCAACGGGCAGCACCCGGACACGCACCACCCGGGCCUCAGCCACUCCUACAUGGACGCGGCGCAGUACCCGCUGCCGGAGGAGGUGGAUGUGCUUUUUAACAUCGACGGUCAAGGCAACCACGUCCCGCCCUACUACGGAAACUCGGUCAGGGCCACGGUGCAGAGGUACCCUCCGACCCACCACGGGAGCCAGGUGUGCCGCCCGCCUCUGCUUCAUGGAUCCCUACCCUGGCUGGACGGCGGCAAAGCCCUGGGCAGCCACCACACCGCCUCCCCCUGGAAUCUCAGCCCCUUCUCCAAGACGUCCAUCCACCACGGCUCCCCGGGGCCCCUCUCCGUCUACCCCCCGGCCUCGUCCUCCUCCUUGUCGGGGGGCCACGCCAGCCCGCACCUCUUCACCUUCCCGCCCACCCCGCCGAAGGACGUCUCCCCGGACCCAUCGCUGUCCACCCCAGGCUCGGCCGGCUCGGCCCGGCAGGACGAGAAAGAGUGCCUCAAGUACCAGGUGCCCCUGCCCGACAGCAUGAAGCUGGAGUCGUCCCACUCCCGUGGCAGCAUGACCGCCCUGGGUGGAGCCUCCUCGUCGACCCACCACCCCAUCACCACCUACCCGCCCUACGUGCCCGAGUACAGCUCCGGACUCUUCCCCCCCAGCAGCCUGCUGGGCGGCUCCCCCACCGGCUUCGGAUGCAAGUCCAGGCCCAAGGCCCGGUCCAGCACAGAAGGCAGGGAGUGUGUGAACUGUGGGGCAACCUCGACCCCACUGUGGCGGCGAGAUGGCACGGGACACUACCUGUGCAACGCCUGCGGGCUCUAUCACAAAAUGAACGGACAGAACCGGCCCCUCAUUAAGCCCAAGCGAAGGCUGUCUGCAGCCAGGAGAGCAGGGACGUCCUGUGCGAACUGUCAGACCACCACAACCACACUCUGGAGGAGGAAUGCCAAUGGGGACCCUGUCUGCAAUGCCUGUGGGCUCUACUACAAGCUUCACAAUAUUAACAGACCCCUGACUAUGAAGAAGGAAGGCAUCCAGACCAGAAACCGAAAAAUGUCUAGCAAAUCCAAAAAGUGCAAAAAAGUGCAUGACUCACUGGAGGACUUCCCCAAGAACAGCUCGUUUAACCCGGCCGCCCUCUCCAGACACAUGUCCUCCCUGAGCCACAUCUCGCCCUUCAGCCACUCCAGCCACAUGCUGACCACGCCCACGCCGAUGCACCCGCCAUCCAGCCUGUCCUUUGGACCACACCACCCCUCCAGCAUGGUCACCGCCAUGGGUUAGAGCCCUGCUCGAUGCUCACAGGGCCCCCAGCGAGAGUCCCUGCAGUCCCUUUCGACUUGCAUUUUUGCAGGAGCAGUAUCAUGAAGCCUAAACGCGAUGGAUAUAUGUUUUUGAAGGCAGAAAGCAAAAUUAUGUUUGCCACUUUGCAAAGGAGCUCACUGUGGUGUCUGUGUUCCAACCACUGAAUCUGGACCCCAUCUGUGAAUAAGCCAUUCUGACUCAUAUCCCCUAUUUAACAGGGUCUCUAGUGCUGUGAAAAAAAAAAUGCUGAACAUUGCAUAUAACUUAUAUUGUAAGAAAUACUGUACAAUGACUUUAUUGCAUCUGGGUAGCUGUAAGGCAUGAAGGAUGCCAAGAAGUUUAAGGAAUAUGGGAGAAAUAGUGUGGAAAUUAAGAAGAAACUAGGUCUGAUAUUCAAAUGGACAAACUGCCAGUUUUGUUUCCUUUCACUGGCCACAGUUGUUUGAUGCAUUAAAAGAAAAUAAAAAAAAGAAAAAAGAGAAAAGAAAAAAAAAGAAAAAAGUUGUAGGCGAAUCAUUUGUUCAAAGCUGUUGGCCUCUGCAAAGGAAAUACCAGUUCUGGGCAAUCAGUGUUACCGUUCACCAGUUGCCGUUGAGGGUUUCAGAGAGCCUUUUUCUAGGCCUACAUGCUUUGUGAACAAGUCCCUGUAAUUGUUGUUUGUAUGUAUAAUUCAAAGCACCAAAAUAAGAAAAGAUGUAGAUUUAUUUCAUCAUAUUAUACAGACCGAACUGUUGUAUAAAUUUAUUUACUGCUAGUCUUAAGAACUGCUUUCUUUCGUUUGUUUGUUUCAAUAUUUUCCUUCUCUCUCAAUUUUUGGUUGAAUAAACUAGAUUACAUUCAGUUGGCCUAAGGUGGUUGUGCUCGGAGGGUUUCUUGUUUCUUUUCCAUUUUGUUUUUGGAUGAUAUUUAUUAAAUAGCUUCUAAGAGUCCGGCGGCAUCUGUCUUGUCCCUAUUCCUGCAGCCUGUGCUGAGGGUAGCAGUGUAUGAGCUACCAGCGUGCAUGUCAGCGACCCUGGCCCGACAGGCCACGUCCUGCAAUCGGCCCGGCUGCCUCUUCGCCCUGUCGUGUUCUGUGUUAGUGAUCACUGCCUUUAAUACAGUCUGUUGGAAUAAUAUUAUAAGCAUAAUAAUAAAGUGAAAAUAUUUUAAAACUA